AGAACGAGCGGCCCUAGGUUUUCGGAAGGGAGGAUCAGGGAUGUUUGCGAGCGGCUGGAACCAGACGGUGCCGAUAGAGGAAGCGGGCUCCAUGGCUGCCCUCCUGCUGCUGCCCCUGCUGCUGUUGCUACCGCUGCUGCUGCUGAAGCUACACCUCUGGCCGCAGUUGCGCUGGCUUCCGGCGGACUUGGCCUUUGCGGUGCGAGCUCUGUGCUGCAAAAGGGCUCUUCGAGCUCGCGCCCUGGCCGCGGCUGCCGCCGACCCGGAAGGUCCCGAGGGGGGCUGCAGCCUGGCCUGGCGCCUCGCGGAACUGGCCCAGCAGCGCGCCGCGCACACCUUUCUCAUUCACGGCUCGCGGCGCUUUAGCUACUCAGAGGCGGAGCGCGAGAGUAACAGGGCUGCACGCGCCUUCCUACGUGCGCUAGGCUGGGACUGGGGACCCGACGGCGGCGACAGCGGCGAGGGGAGCGCUGGAGAAGGCGAGCGGGCAGCGCCGGGAGCCGGAGAUGCAGCGGCCGGAAGCGGCGCGGAGUUUGCCGGAGGGGACGGUGCCGCCAGAGGUGGAGGAGCCGCCGCCCCUCUGUCACCUGGAGCAACUGUGGCGCUGCUCCUCCCCGCUGGCCCAGAGUUUCUGUGGCUCUGGUUCGGGCUGGCCAAGGCCGGCCUGCGCACUGCCUUUGUGCCCACCGCCCUGCGCCGGGGCCCCCUGCUGCACUGCCUCCGCAGCUGCGGCGCGCGCGCGCUGGUGCUGGCGCCAGAGUUUCUGGAGUCCCUGGAGCCGGACCUGCCCGCCCUGAGAGCCAUGGGGCUCCACCUGUGGGCUGCAGGCCCAGGAACCCACCCUGCUGGAAUUAGCGAUUUGCUGGCUGAAGUGUCCGCUGAAGUGGAUGGGCCAGUGCCAGGAUACCUCUCUUCCCCCCAGAGCAUAACAGACACGUGCCUGUACAUCUUCACCUCUGGCACCACGGGCCUCCCCAAGGCUGCUCGGAUCAGUCAUCUGAAGAUCCUGCAAUGCCAGGGCUUCUAUCAGCUGUGUGGUGUCCACCAGGAAGAUGUGAUCUACCUCGCCCUCCCACUCUACCACAUGUCCGGUUCCCUGCUGGGCAUCGUGGGCUGCAUGGGCAUUGGGGCCACAGUGGUGCUGAAAUCCAAGUUCUCGGCUGGUCAGUUCUGGGAAGAUUGCCAGCAGCACAGGGUGACGGUGUUCCAGUACAUUGGGGAGCUGUGCCGAUACCUUGUCAACCAGCCCCCGAGCAAGGCAGAACGUGGCCAUAAGGUCCGGCUGGCAGUGGGCAGCGGGCUGCGCCCAGAUACCUGGGAGCGUUUUGUGCGGCGCUUCGGGCCCCUGCAGGUGCUGGAGACAUAUGGACUGACAGAGGGCAACGUGGCCACCAUCAACUACACAGGACAGCGGGGCGCUGUGGGGCGUGCUUCCUGGCUUUACAAGCAUAUCUUCCCCUUCUCCUUGAUUCGCUAUGAUGUCACCACAGGAGAGCCAAUUCGGGACCCCCAGGGGCACUGUAUGGCCACAUCUCCAGGUGAGCCAGGGCUGCUGGUGGCCCCGGUAAGCCAGCAGUCCCCAUUCCUGGGCUAUGCUGGCGGGCCAGAGCUGGCCCAGGGGAAGUUGCUAAAGGAUGUCUUCCGGCCUGGGGAUGUUUUCUUCAACACUGGGGACCUGCUGGUCUGCGAUGACCAAGGUUUUCUCCGCUUCCAUGAUCGUACUGGAGACACCUUCAGGUGGAAGGGGGAGAAUGUGGCCACAACCGAGGUGGCAGAGGUCUUCGAGGCCCUAGAUUUUCUUCAGGAGGUGAACGUCUAUGGAGUCACUGUGCCAGGGCAUGAAGGCAGGGCUGGAAUGGCAGCCCUAGUUCUGCGUCCCCCCCACGCUUUGGACCUUAUGCAGCUCUACACCCACGUGUCUGAGAACUUGCCACCUUAUGCCCGGCCCCGAUUCCUCAGGCUCCAGGAGUCUUUGGCCACCACAGAGACCUUCAAACAGCAGAAAGUUCGGAUGGCAAAUGAGGGCUUCGACCCCAGCACCCUGUCUGACCCACUGUACGUUCUGGACCAGGCUGUAGGUGCCUACCUGCCCCUCACAACUGCCCGGUACAGCGCCCUCCUGGCAGGAAACCUUCGAAUCUGAGAACUUCCACACCUGAGGCACCUGAGAGAGGAACUCUGUGGGGUGGGGGCCGUUGCAGGUGUACUGGGCUGUCAGGGAUCUUUUCUAUACCAGAACUGCGGUCACUAUUUUGUAAUAAAUGUGGCUGGAGCUGAUCCAGCUGUCUCUGACCUACA